AGCGUCGGCUCUGGCAGCACUGGAGGCGGCGGCGGCCCGAGGGCGACUUGCGGGGCGCGCAGGCCGCCGUGCACCCGGGACGCUUCCCCCUCGGGGACCCUCCGCGGGCUUCUCCGCCGCGCCGUCCGGCGGGAGCCGGCGGGACCCCGGGCGAGCGGCGCGGGCGGCACCAUGAGGCGGCAGUGGGGCGCGCUGCUGCUUGGCGCCCUGCUCUGCGCACACGGCCUGGCCAGCAGCCCCGAGUGUGCUUGUGGUCGGAGCCACUUCACAUGUGCAGUGAGUGCUCUUGGAGAGUGUACCUGCAUCCCUGCCCAGUGGCAGUGUGAUGGAGACAAUGACUGCGGGGACCACAGCGAUGAGGAUGGAUGUAUACUACCUACCUGUUCCCCUCUUGACUUUCACUGUGACAAUGGCAAGUGCAUCCGCCGCUCCUGGGUGUGUGACGGGGACAACGACUGUGAGGAUGACUCGGAUGAGCAGGACUGUCCCCCCCGGGAGUGUGAGGAGGACGAGUUUCCCUGCCAGAAUGGCUACUGCAUCCGGAGUCUGUGGCACUGCGAUGGUGACAAUGACUGUGGCGACAACAGCGAUGAGCAGUGUGACAUGCGCAAGUGCUCCGACAAGGAGUUCCGCUGUAGUGACGGAAGCUGCAUUGCUGAGCAUUGGUACUGCGACGGUGACACCGACUGCAAAGAUGGCUCCGAUGAGGAGAACUGUCCCUCAGCAGUGCCAGCGCCCCCCUGCAACCUGGAGGAGUUCCAGUGUGCCUAUGGACGCUGCAUCCUCGACAUCUACCACUGCGAUGGCGACGAUGACUGUGGAGACUGGUCAGACGAGUCUGACUGCUCCUCCCACCAGCCCUGCCGCUCUGGGGAGUUCAUGUGUGACAGUGGCCUGUGCAUCAAUGCAGGCUGGCGCUGCGAUGGUGACGCGGACUGUGAUGACCAGUCUGAUGAGCGCAACUGCACCACCUCCAUGUGUACGGCAGAACAGUUCCGCUGUCACUCAGGCCGCUGUGUCCGCCUGUCCUGGCGCUGUGAUGGGGAGGACGACUGUGCAGACAACAGCGAUGAAGAGAACUGUGAGAAUACAGGAAGCCCCCAAUGUGCCUUGGACCAGUUCCUGUGUUGGAAUGGGCGCUGCAUUGGGCAGAGGAAGCUGUGCAACGGGGUCAACGACUGUGGUGACAACAGCGACGAAAGCCCACAGCAGAAUUGCCGGCCCCGGACGGGUGAGGAGAACUGCAAUGUUAACAACGGUGGCUGUGCCCAGAAGUGCCAGAUGGUGCGGGGGGCAGUGCAGUGUACCUGCCACACAGGCUACCGGCUCACAGAGGAUGGGCACACGUGCCAAGAUGUGAAUGAAUGUGCCGAGGAGGGGUAUUGCAGCCAGGGCUGCACCAACAGCGAAGGGGCUUUCCAAUGCUGGUGUGAAACAGGCUAUGAACUACGGCCCGACCGGCGCAGCUGCAAGGCUCUGGGGCCAGAGCCUGUGCUGCUGUUCGCCAAUCGCAUCGACAUCCGGCAGGUGCUGCCACACCGCUCUGAGUACACACUGCUGCUUAACAACCUGGAGAAUGCCAUUGCCCUUGAUUUCCACCACCGCCGCGAGCUUGUCUUCUGGUCAGAUGUCACCCUGGACCGGAUCCUCCGUGCCAACCUCAACGGCAGCAACGUGGAGGAGGUUGUGUCUACUGGGCUGGAGAGCCCAGGGGGCCUGGCUGUGGAUUGGGUCCAUGACAAACUCUACUGGACCGACUCAGGCACCUCGAGGAUUGAGGUGGCCAAUCUGGAUGGGGCCCACCGGAAAGUGUUGCUGUGGCAGAACCUGGAGAAGCCCCGGGCCAUUGCCUUGCAUCCCAUGGAGGGUACCAUUUACUGGACAGACUGGGGCAACACCCCCCGUAUUGAGGCCUCCAGCAUGGAUGGCUCUGGACGCCGCAUCAUUGCCGAUACCCAUCUCUUCUGGCCCAAUGGCCUCACCAUCGACUAUGCCGGGCGCCGUAUGUACUGGGUGGAUGCUAAGCACCAUGUCAUCGAGAGGGCCAAUCUGGAUGGGAGUCACCGUAAGGCUGUCAUUAGCCAGGGCCUCCCGCAUCCCUUCGCCAUCACAGUGUUUGAAGACAGCCUGUACUGGACAGACUGGCACACCAAGAGCAUCAAUAGCGCUAACAAAUUUACGGGGAAGAACCAGGAAAUCAUUCGCAACAAACUCCACUUCCCUAUGGACAUCCACACCUUGCACCCCCAGCGCCAACCUGCAGGGAAAAACCGCUGUGGGGACAACAACGGAGGCUGCACGCACCUGUGUCUGCCCAGUGGCCAGAACUACACCUGUGCCUGCCCCACUGGCUUCCGCAAGAUCAGCAGCCACGCCUGUGCCCAGAGUCUUGACAAGUUCCUGCUUUUUGCCCGAAGGAUGGACAUCCGUCGAAUCAGCUUUGACACAGAGGACCUGUCUGAUGAUGUCAUCCCACUGGCUGACGUGCGCAGUGCUGUGGCCCUUGACUGGGACUCCCGGGAUGACCACGUGUACUGGACAGAUGUCAGCACUGAUACCAUCAGCAGGGCCAAGUGGGAUGGAACAGGACAGGAGGUGGUAGUGGAUACCAGUUUGGAGAGCCCAGCUGGCCUGGCCAUUGAUUGGGUCACCAACAAACUGUACUGGACAGAUGCAGGUACAGACCGGAUUGAAGUAGCCAACACAGAUGGCAGCAUGAGAACAGUACUCAUCUGGGAGAACCUUGAUCGUCCUCGGGACAUCGUGGUGGAACCCAUGGGCGGGUACAUGUAUUGGACUGACUGGGGUGCGAGCCCCAAGAUUGAACGAGCUGGCAUGGAUGCCUCAGGCCGCCAAGUCAUUAUCUCUUCUAAUCUGACCUGGCCUAAUGGGUUAGCUAUUGAUUAUGGGUCCCAGCGUCUAUACUGGGCUGACGCCGGCAUGAAGACAAUUGAAUUUGCUGGACUGGAUGGCAGUAAGAGGAAGGUGCUGAUUGGAAGCCAGCUCCCCCACCCAUUUGGGCUGACCCUCUAUGGAGAGCGCAUCUAUUGGACUGACUGGCAGACCAAGAGCAUACAGAGCGCUGACCGGCUGACAGGGCUGGACCGGGAGACUCUGCAGGAGAACCUGGAAAACCUAAUGGACAUCCAUGUCUUCCACCGCCGCCGGCCCCCAGUGUCUACACCAUGUGCUAUGGAGAAUGGCGGCUGUAGCCACCUGUGUCUUAGGUCCCCAAAUCCAAGCGGAUUCAGCUGUACCUGCCCCACAGGCAUCAACCUGCUGUCUGAUGGCAAGACCUGCUCACCAGGCAUGAACAGUUUCCUCAUCUUCGCCAGGAGGAUAGACAUUCGCAUGGUCUCCCUGGACAUCCCUUAUUUUGCUGAUGUGGUGGUACCAAUCAACAUUACCAUGAAGAACACCAUUGCCAUUGGAGUAGACCCCCAGGAAGGAAAGGUGUACUGGUCUGACAGCACACUGCACAGGAUCAGUCGUGCCAAUCUGGAUGGCUCACAGCAUGAGGACAUCAUCACCACAGGGCUACAGACCACAGAUGGGCUCGCGGUUGAUGCCAUUGGCCGGAAAGUAUACUGGACAGACACGGGAACAAACCGGAUUGAAGUGGGCAACCUGGACGGGUCCAUGCGGAAAGUGUUGGUGUGGCAGAACCUUGACAGUCCCCGGGCCAUCGUACUGUACCAUGAGAUGGGGUUUAUGUACUGGACAGACUGGGGGGAGAAUGCCAAGUUAGAGCGGUCCGGAAUGGAUGGCUCAGACCGCGCGGUGCUCAUCAACAACAACCUAGGAUGGCCCAAUGGACUGACUGUGGACAAGGCCAGCUCCCAACUGCUAUGGGCCGAUGCCCACACCGAGCGAAUUGAGGCUGCUGACCUGAAUGGUGCCAAUCGGCAUACAUUGGUGUCACCGGUGCAGCACCCAUAUGGCCUCACCCUGCUCGACUCCUAUAUCUACUGGACUGACUGGCAGACUCGGAGCAUCCACCGUGCUGACAAGGGUACUGGCAGCAAUGUCAUCCUCGUGAGGUCCAACCUGCCAGGCCUCAUGGACAUGCAGGCUGUGGACCGGGCACAGCCACUAGGUUUUAACAAGUGCGGCUCGAGAAAUGGCGGCUGCUCCCACCUCUGCUUGCCUCGGCCUUCUGGCUUCUCCUGUGCCUGCCCCACUGGCAUCCAGCUGAAGGGAGAUGGGAAGACCUGUGAUCCCUCUCCUGAGACCUACCUGCUCUUCUCCAGCCGUGGCUCCAUCCGGCGUAUCUCACUGGACACCAGUGACCACACCGAUGUGCAUGUCCCUGUUCCUGAGCUCAACAAUGUCAUCUCCCUGGACUAUGACAGCGUGGAUGGAAAGGUCUAUUACACAGAUGUGUUCCUGGAUGUUAUCAGGCGAGCAGACCUGAACGGCAGCAACAUGGAGACAGUGAUCGGGCGAGGGCUGAAGACCACUGACGGGCUGGCAGUGGACUGGGUGGCCAGGAACCUGUACUGGACAGACACAGGUCGAAAUACCAUUGAGGCGUCCAGGCUGGAUGGUUCCUGCCGCAAAGUACUGAUCAACAAUAGCCUGGAUGAGCCCCGGGCCAUUGCUGUUUUCCCCAGGAAGGGGUACCUCUUCUGGACAGACUGGGGCCACAUUGCCAAGAUCGAACGGGCAAACUUGGAUGGUUCUGAGCGGAAGGUCCUCAUCAACACAGACCUGGGUUGGCCCAAUGGCCUUACCCUGGACUAUGAUACCCGCAGGAUCUACUGGGUGGAUGCGCAUCUGGACCGGAUCGAGAGUGCUGACCUCAAUGGGAAACUGCGGCAGGUCUUGGUCAGCCAUGUGUCCCACCCCUUUGCCCUCACACAGCAAGACAGGUGGAUCUACUGGACAGACUGGCAGACCAAGUCAAUCCAGCGUGUUGACAAAUACUCAGGCCGGAACAAGGAGACAGUGCUGGCAAAUGUGGAAGGACUCAUGGAUAUCAUCGUGGUUUCCCCUCAGCGGCAGACAGGGACCAAUGCCUGUGGUGUGAACAAUGGUGGCUGCACCCACCUCUGCUUUGCCAGAGCCUCGGACUUCGUAUGUGCCUGUCCUGACGAACCUGAUAGCCGGCCCUGCUCCCUUGUGCCUGGCCUGGUACCACCAGCUCCUAGGGCUACUGGCAUGAGUGAAAAGAGCCCAGUGCUACCCAACACACCACCUACCACCUUGUAUUCUUCAACCACCCGGACCCGCACGUCUCUGGAGGAGGUGGAAGGAAGAUGCUCUGAAAGGGAUGCCAGGCUGGGCCUCUGUGCACGUUCCAAUGACGCUGUUCCUGCUGCUCCAGGGGAAGGACUUCAUAUCAGCUACGCCAUUGGUGGACUCCUCAGUAUUCUGCUGAUUUUGGUGGUGAUUGCAGCUUUGAUGCUGUACAGACACAAAAAAUCCAAGUUCACUGAUCCUGGAAUGGGGAACCUCACCUACAGCAACCCCUCCUACCGAACAUCCACACAGGAAGUGAAGAUUGAAGCAAUCCCCAAACCAGCCAUGUACAACCAGCUGUGCUAUAAGAAAGAGCAGCUCUUUCACCCCUCUGAUAGUCUUUCACCUUUUCUCUUCUGAUUUCCUCUUGAUUUCAGGGAGGGCCUGACCAUAACUACACCAAGGAGAAGAUCAAGAUCGUAGAGGGAAUCUGCCUCCUGUCUGGGGAUGAUGCUGAGUGGGAUGACCUCAAGCAACUGCGAAGCUCACGGGGGGGCCUCCUCCGGGAUCAUGUAUGCAUGAAGACAGACACGGUGUCCAUCCAGGCCAGCUCUGGCUCCCUGGAUGACACAGAGACGGAGCAGCUGUUACAGGAAGAGCAGUCUGAGUGUAGCAGCGUCCAUACUGCAGCCACUCCAGAAAGACGAGGCUCUCUGCCAGACACGGGCUGGAAACAUGAACGCAAGCUCUCCUCAGAGAGCCAGGUCUAAAUGCCCACAUUCUCUUCCCUGCCUGCCUGUUCCUUCUCCUUUAUGGACGUCUAGUCCUUGUGCUCGCUUACACCGCAGGCCCCGCUUCUGUGUGCUUGUCCUCCUCCUCCUCCCACCCCAUAACUGUUCCUAAGCCUUCACCGGAGCUGUUUACCACGUGAGUCCAUAACUACCUGUGCACAAGAAAUGAUGGCACAUCACGAGAAUUUAGACCUGGAUUUUACCAUGAACCUCACAUCUUGUACUCCAUCCUGGGCCCCCUGAAACUGCUUAUUCGUGAUUCCUCACCAGCGUAGAGCUCCACCUCCCCUUUCCCCAGUACCCUCAGUGCCUGCUUCUCAGUGCUGAUGCAGCUGAUGACCCAGGACUGCGCUCUGCCCCAUCACAGCCAGCAUGACUGCUUCUCUGAGAGAACUUGCCCAUCAGGGGCUGGGACAUGGGGGUGUGGGUAAAGACAGGGAUGAAGGAUAGAGGCUGAGAGAAGAAGGAAGAAUCAGCCCAGCAGGUAUGGGCAUCUGGGAAACCUCCAGCCUCAAGUGUGUUAGUAACAUGAAAAAGCUUUGGGGGGUAGUUGGAUCUGGGUGUCUGGUCCAUUGCUGGCAGUGGACAUUAUUCUUGCCCUAAGAGACACUGCCUUUUCAGCAGCAGAUACUGGUGAGAUGGGGGUGGCUCAGGCUGUUCUUCCUCCUCCUAGAAUGUCUGGAGCUGUUUCUACAUUCAGAUAACUGGGUCCCCUAUCACAAGGCUACUGGCUAAUAGGAAUUCCCUCCUGGUGCCACCACUGGCCAGUACCUUUCCUAAGUCUUUGCUCAAAUUAACCAGGUUGUGAGCCAGUGGCUUGAGUGAAUGUUAGGCCUUGGGGGCUGAGUCUCUGAAAAGUCUAAGAAGCUCUGCCUAGACCAAAUAUGGUAUACCUCCUGACCCCUCUCUCCCUCAUGUCCUGGGAUUCUGGGGAAGAGACCUAGAAACAAGCUUUCAAAGAAAAACCAGAAGUUGUCAUAAAUGGUCAGAAAGAACGAUCAGGUUGGAGACUUGGGAAACCCAGGGCCUAAAGAGAAGUAUCCAUGAGGGUCAAACUUCCUGUUGAACUUCCUAUGUUCUUUCUCAAGUGCUCAGGGAUCUAAGUUAGUGGACAGCAAGCCUGUGGCUACGGGGUGGUGAUGUUCCUCUUCCAGCUGUCCCCUCAGCUAAGGGGCUUAGUUUCCAUGUGGGAUGCCAUCACUUGGUUCAUGCUCAUUCACACAAAGGGCACGUGUCUCAGCCUGGUAUCAGGGAAAUUGAGACUUAUUUUUGCCCUAAAACGUCUCCCUAGCUGUUCUUCGUGGGGUUUUUUUGUUUGUUUUUUUGCCUAAUUUGCUUUUUCUGACCAAGCCUUGUGGCACCAGCAAUCUCCAAAGUCCUGUGGUGGGAGGGCUGAAUAAAUAAAAAUACAAAGAGGUGGGUAAGGAGUAGGAAGGUAGAGAGCACCACUGAUGAGGCCCUCCUAGCCCAUGGCAGACCCAGACCUCUUCUCCCCCAGGAAUUAGAAGUGGCAGGAGAGAACAACAGGGGCUGGGAAUGGAGGGGAGAAUUUCUAGGGGAAGUUUCCUGAGUUGAAACUUCUCCUGUGGUUACUGGUAUUGAGAAAUCAGCUACCAAAGUGAAAAAGGACAAGAUCAAUUCUUUUCUAGUCAGUUCUAAGACUGCUAGAGAGAGAUACCAGGCCCUUAGCCUUGCUCUCAGUAGCGUCAGCCCCAGUUCUGAGCCUCCCCACAUUACACUUAACAAGCAGUAAAGGAGUGAGCACUUUGGGUCCUUAGACUCACGUCUGGGGAGGAAGAGCAAGUAGAAAAGUGGCAUUUUCUUGAUUGGAAAGGGGGAAGGAUCUUAUUGCACUUGGGCUGUUCAGAAUGUAGAAAGGACAUAUUUGAGGAAGUAUCUAUUUGAGCACUGAUUUACUCUGUAAAAAGCAAAAUCUCUCUGUCCUAAACUAAUGGAAGCGAUUCUCCCAUGCUCAUGUGUAAUGGUUUUAACGUUACUCACUGGAGAGAUUGGACUUUCUGGAGUUAUUUAACCACUAUGUUCAGUAUUUUAGGACUUUAUGAUAAUUUAAUAUAAAUUUAGCUUUUCUUAAUCACCUUGCCUGGCUUGGAGUCAUGACUAAUCCUGCACCUGCUCUGUCUGGCAGACCCAUGCUGUGGAAAACCUGCUUACAGACAUCACUUUUAAGUCCUUUGUGGAUGUGGGCACAGUGAAGAGCAAUAAAGAGUGUGAGGUUCCUGCUGGA